AACGUCAUCUAGGAGCACCGAGCAGCUUGGCUAAAAGUAAGGGUGUCGUGCUGAUGGCCCUGUGCGCACUGACCCGCGCUCUGCGCUCUCUGAACCUGGCGCCCCCGACCGUCGCCGCCCCUGCCCCGAGUCUGUUCCCCGCCGCCCAGGUAAUCCAUCUUACCCGGGAAGAAGGCUGCUUCCAUUCGGGCUGCCGGAGAUGGGGUCUGCGGGCAUGCGAGGCGGGAGUUGCGAGUCUGGUCAGGAGUCAUGCAGAUGAUGAACAAUGGCCUCCUCCAACAGCCCUCUGCCUUGAUGUUGCUCCCCUGCCGCCCAGUUCUUACUUCUGUGGCCCUUAAUGCCAACUUUGUGUCCUGGAAGAGUCGUACCAAGUACACCAUUACACCAGUGAAGAUGAGGAAGUCUGGGGGCCGAGACCACACAGGCCGAAUCCGGGUGCAUGGUAUUGGCGGGGGCCACAAGCAACGUUAUCGAAUGAUUGACUUUCUGCGUUUCCGGCCUGAGGAGACCAAGUCAGGACCCUUUGAGGAGAAGGUUAUCCAAGUCCGCUAUGAUCCCUGUAGGUCAGCAGACAUAGCUCUGGUUGCUGGGGGCAGCCGGAAACGCUGGAUCAUCGCCACAGAAAACAUGCAGGCUGGAGAUACAAUCUUGAACUCUAACCACAUAGGCCGAAUGGCAGUUGCUGCUCGGGAAGGGGAUGCGCAUCCUCUUGGGGCUCUGCCUGUGGGGACCCUCAUCAACAACGUGGAAAGUGAGCCAGGCCGGGGUGCCCAAUAUAUCCGAGCUGCAGGGACGUGUGGUGUGCUACUGCGGAAGGUGAAUGGCACAGCCAUUAUCCAGCUGCCCUCUAAGAGGCAGAUGCAGGUGCUGGAAACGUGCGUAGCAACAGUAGGCCGAGUAUCCAACGUUGAUCAUAACAAACGGGUCAUUGGCAAGGCAGGUCGCAACCGCUGGCUGGGCAAGAGGCCUAACAGUGGGCGGUGGCACCGCAAGGGGGGCUGGGCUGGCCGAAAGAUUCGGCCACUACCCCCCAUGAAGAGUUACGUGAAGCUGCCUUCUGCUUCUGCCCAAAGCUGAUAUCCCUGUACUCUAAUAAAAUGCCCCCCCCCCCCGUUUUAAUCUGUUACUGUGGUUUUGUUUUGGGUGUUUUUUGUUUUUUUUGUUGUUGUUUUUUUUUUGCGGGGGAGGGGAUGGUACAGACUAAACGUGGGGAAAAGAAGUAAAAAGUGUGGAAGAGAAAGUACAGGACACUGGGUCUGUCCCCACCCCAAUUCCCUUACAAGUAAUGGAGCCGGGGAUGGAAAUAAAUGACGUCCAAGGUC